CACACUGGCUGUUGUCAUCCGCCCCUGAGGUUUCAGGCUGUCGGCAGUGAAGGUCAGAGUGCAGACCUGAGACCACUGCUCACCGAUUUCAGACUCCAGUUUAUCUGUGCCUCGGCUUCCCCACUUAGUCGCAGAAGACUUAGGCUGAGGCCCCAGGAAGAGAUCUCCAUCCUUUGCAGGAGCACAACAAGAUGGCCAUGUCCCAGGAAUCAUUGACCUUCAAGGACGUGUUUGUGGACUUCACCCUGGAGGAGUGGCAGCAACUGGACUCUGCCCAGAAGAACCUCUACAGGGAUGUCAUGCUUGAGAACUACAGCCACCUGGUGUCCGUGGGGCAUCUAGUUGGGAAGCCAGAUGUGAUCUUCAGGUUGGGACCAGGUGACGAGUCCUGGAUGGCAGAUGGAGGGACCCCGGUACGGACCUGUGCAGGUGAGGACAGGCCAGAAGUCUGGGAAGUUGACGAGCAGAUAGAUCACUACAAGGAAAGCCAAGACAAAUUUCUGUGGCAAGCUGCAUUCAUAGGCAAGGAAACACUGAAGGAUGAAAGUGGUCAAGAAUGUAAAAUAUGUAGAAAAAUCAUUUAUCUCAACACAGACUUUGUUUCUGUAAAACAAAGACUCCCUAAAUAUUAUUCAUGGGAAAGGUGUUCAAAACAUCAUUUAAACUUUCUUGGUCAAAAUAGAAGCUAUGUAAGAAAGAAAGAUGAUGGAUGUAAGGCAUAUUGGAAAGUAUGCCUCCAUUAUAAUCUUCAUAAAGCUCAACCUGCAGAGAGAUUUUUUGACCCUAAUCAACGAGGGAAAGCCCUCCACCAAAAGCAAGCCCUUAGAAAAAGUCAGAGAAGUCAAACUGGGGAGAAACUCUACAAAUGUACUGAAUGUGGAAAAGUGUUUAUCCAGAAAGCAAACUUAGUUGUACAUCAAAGAACUCACACCGGAGAGAAACCUUAUGAAUGCUGCGAAUGUGCAAAAGCCUUCAGCCAGAAGUCAACCCUCAUAGCACACCAGAGAACUCACACAGGGGAGAAGCCCUAUGAAUGCAGUGAAUGUGGAAAAACCUUUAUCCAGAAGUCAACUCUGAUUAAACAUCAACGAACUCAUACAGGAGAGAAACCAUUUGUAUGUGACAAAUGUCCAAAAGCCUUUAAGAGUUCAUAUCAUCUUAUUAGACAUGAAAAAACACACAUUAGACAAGCAUUUUAUAAAGGUAUUAAAUGUACUACGUCCAGCCUUAUAUAUCAAAGAAUUCACACAAGUGAGAAACCUCAGUGCAGUGAACAUGGGAAAGCCUCUGAUGAGAAGCCCAGUCCCACUAAACAUUGGAGAACUCAUACAAAAGAGAACAUUUAUGAGUGUAGUAAAUGUGGGAAAAGCUUCAGAGGAAAGUCACACCUCUCUGUUCAUCAGAGAAUUCAUACAGGAGAGAAACCCUAUGAAUGUAGUAUAUGUGGGAAGACUUUCAGUGGAAAGUCACACCUCUCUGUCCAUCAUAGAACUCAUACAGGAGAGAAACCUUAUGAAUGCAGAAGAUGUGGGAAAGCCUUUGGGGAGAAGUCAACCCUUAUUGUACAUCAGAGAAUGCAUACAGGAGAGAAACCCUAUAAAUGCAACGAAUGUGGGAAAGCCUUUAGUGAGAAGUCACCACUGAUUAAACAUCAGAGAAUUCAUACAGGAGAGAGACCCUAUGAAUGCACUGACUGUAAAAAAGCCUUCAGUAGGAAGUCAACUCUCAUCAAACAUCAGAGAAUUCAUACAGGAGAAAAACCUUACAAAUGUAGUGAAUGUGGGAAGGCCUUCAGUGUGAAAUCAACUCUCAUUGUGCAUCACAGAACUCAUACAGGAGAGAAACCUUAUGAAUGCAGAGACUGUGGGAAAGCAUUCAGUGGGAAGUCAACUCUCAUUAAACAUCAGAGAAGUCACACAGGAGAUAAAAACCUAUGAUUAUACUUGAGAGUGGGAUAAUUAUACUAGUAGUUAUUUGUCAUUUGACUAUUACUAGUCUCAUUAUUUGUCAAAUAAUCAUGGCGAGUAAUCUUAUAAAUGUCCAGAAUAUUGGAAAUUCUUCAUAUGUUAAUGUUCAUUUAACUUAAUACAAAGUACAAAAGUAUAAUUCCAGAGGUGUCAAUAAAUGUGAUCAGUUUUUUCACCCAGAAUUCUUCACCCAGGAGUGAAGAACUGUAUGUCAAAUAAUUCAAAAGGGGCAAAACUGAAUGUAGUUAUGUGGGAAAGCCUUCAGAAAUAAUUUAAAUGGCACUGUUUAUCAGAGUAUGUAUGCCGAGGAAAACUAAGAAUUUAGUGAGCUUAUAAAACCAUGGUAGCCAGGCGUGGUACGUAGCUCACACCUGUAAUCCUAGCACUUUUGGGAGGCUGAGGUGGGCAGAUUGCUUGAGCUCACAAGUUUGAGACCAGCCUGGGCAACAUGGCAAAACUCUGUCUCUACAAAAAAUACAAAAGUUAUCUGAGUGUAGUGGUGCAUACCUUUAGUCCCAGCUACUCAGGAGGUUGAAGUAGGAGGGUGGCUUGAGCCCAGGAGGCAGAGGUUGCAGUGAACUGAGAUCGUGCCACUGCACUCCAGCCUGGGCAUUAUAGCCAGACCUUGUCAAAUAAAUAAAUAAACAAACCCAUGGUAUAAAUGAGAGGAAUCAUGCUCUAUAUUCUUUUAUUAAUAGAGACAGGGUCUUGCUAUGUUGCCCAGGCUGGUCUUGAACUCGUAGCGUUAAUUGAUCCUCCCACCUUUGCCUCCCAAAGCACUUGUAUUAUAGAUAUGAGCCACCACACUUACCAUGUUCUUUACCAAACAUUUUGUGGAAGAGGUGUAGAGGUGGCAAACAAUUAUAAAUUUAAGAUAUGUUCACUGUGGAGUAGAGUAUGAUUAUUUAUUUAUUUAGAGAUGGAGUUUCGCUCUUCUCGCCCAGGCUGGAGUGCAGUGGCACGAUCUUGGCUCACUGCAGCCUCUGCCUUCCAGGUUCAAGUGAUUCUCCUGCCUCAGCCUCCCAAGUAGCUGGGAUUACAGGCACCCACCACCACACCCGGCUAAUUCUUUUUUUUUUUUUUUUUUUUUAGUAGAGACGCAGUUUUGCCAUGUUGGGCAGGCUGGUCUCGAACUCCUGACCUCAGGUAAUCCGCCCGCCUCAGCCUCCCAAAGUGCUGGGAUUAUAGGCGAGAGCCACCACGCUCAGUGAGUAUGACAUUUUUAAAAGAACAGUAUAAAGCAUAAAAUAUCCCAUGUGGGGCAAACUCCCAGAUUAUUUUCCUAAACAAAUAGAAAAAAUGCUUCCUGAAAUAGGGUAAGAGAGGAUGAGUCAUCAGGAUCCCUGAAACAAAGAUCUCAAACAGGAGACCUUACGUAUAUUAUUCAUCAAUAUCUUCAGUGCAAAAAUGCAAAGCCAUUACAGAAAGGGCACAUAGUAAGCUUUUACAUACUUUCCUUAGGAACAGUGCUUAGAACUUAAAAUUCUCCAUGUUUUAAUAAAGAGUAAUAAUUUUAUGGUGAAGCAAUAUAAGAUUUAAAAUUUUCAGAGUAUCUUCCAUAACAGCAGUAUUAUUUAAAGUAGUGAAAAAAUAAGACAAUUUAAUAUCCAAUGAUAGAUGAUUAAAAAUUGGUAUGUCAGGUGAAAUAACAUGCACCAAUUAAGACUACUGGCAAAUUUGGGAAAAUGUUCGUGGUAAAUCAUUAGGUAAAAAAUAUUAUAAAACAAUAACCAUAUGAUUAAUAUUGUACAAACAGGAAGUAUAUGAACCAUUAUAUCAGUGAUUCUGGGUGGUUGACAUAUAAAAAUUUUGUGAUGAGUAAAGUUAUAUGCACAUAUAAGUAUAAAUUUGUAUUUAUUUAAGUAUAAAUUUGUAUUCACCUAUUUCAUAGGUGAGUGUGUGUGUAUAGAUAAACACAUGGAACAAAAAGUUAGGUAUAUCUGUGUAGUGUGGAGGGAAAAAGCUAGGAAAGAAAUACACCAAAUUAUUAAGUAAAUUGGCAUUUGAAUGUGGGGAUUAUUGAUGUGUAAAAAUUUUUUUGAUUGUAGUCUCCAGAAAUCACCAAUAAAGUAUAUCGUUUAAAGUGUA